CCCUUUCCCACCCCUCGGAGUAGAGCUGCACAUGCGGCUGCUCCCUGCUCCGUCCCGCCCAGCCACUGUCGCGCAGGAACGGGUCCCUGCAGCCCCCAGCCGAUGGCAGGACAGUAGCCGCCUGUCAGAGGUCGUGAACGGCUGAGGCAGACGCAGCGGCUCCCGGGCCUCAAGAGAGUGGGUGUCUCCGGAGGCCAUGGGCUACCCGGAGGUGGAGCGCAGGGAACUCCUGCCUGCAGCAGCGCCGCGGGAGCGAGGGAGCCAGGGCUGCGGGUGUGGCGGGGCCCCUGCCCGGGCGGGCGAAGGGAACAGCUGCCUGCUCUUCCUGGGUUUCUUUGGCCUCUCGCUGGCCCUCCACCUGCUGACGUUGUGCUGCUACCUAGAGUUGCGCUCGGAGUUGCGGCGGGAACGUGGAGCCGAGUCCCGCCUUGGCGGCUCGGGCACCCCUGGCACCUCUGGCACCCUAAGCAGCCUCGGUGGCCUCGACCCUGACAGCCCCAUCACCAGUCACCUUGGGCAGCCGUCACCUAAGCAGCAGCCAUUGGAACCGGGAGAAGCCGCACUCCACUCUGACUCCCAGGACGGGCACCAGAGCUGAUGCCAGAACCAGCAGGCUCCCCUUUGGAGUUGGAGCUGUAAACAGCUGUAAUAACUGUUCCACGCCCGCCCGUUGAAACAACUUUUAACCGCAUUUUCAGCGCGGGUCCUUGUGCGCUGACCAGAACGUGGGCUUGUUCACACUUACCUGCAAUUUGAGACUGAUUGUCCUCGGCGUUCUAGUGAGGAUCAGCGCCCCUGAGGAAUUCUGGUAGAAAUAUGCCGUCUUGCUAGACAACUUCUGAACAGCAAUUUUAAAAAUCUAUGGAAAUAAAACUCACCCUUUGCAUGCCGGUUCUGAUUCUUAAGCGGGGUAGGUGUGCGGUGGGAAGGGUGGGUGGGAAGCGCUUUUACUACUGUUAGCUUGAGAACGGGAAUCUGCCAAUGGAAUAAUUACUCAGGACUCGUCCCCCAAGAGCAGUUUUGUUUGUUUUUGCAAUCUUUAUGGUGUUUGUGCCCUAAUAAGCAAACUAUUAGCUUUGGUGUUUGUUUUCUAUUCUAUUCUUUCUAGCUUUUUAUUCAAGUAAAUUUCGUUCACUUAACGUAAAUACUGUCUUGGUUGCCAUAUGUGAAACUUAGGAGAAGCAUCCAAGGAUCCUUUCGAGGUGGCUAAAGAAUAAUAAUAAAAUUGUACCUCUUAGGGAAGAGAGCAAGUUGUACAAAUAAGUUCCUUGAGGUGAGGGACCCAAGCCUUCUAUAUUUACUGCCACAUCCAGAGUCAUUGUCACAACUCUGUAAACAUUAUUUGUGCCACUUUGACCUCCCAUCUAAAGUGGUACGCUUGAUAGAGACAUCAUAUUCAUGAUAAUAGUGUAAUGUUAGGACUGAUACUUAAAAAAAAAAAAAAAGAUGUGCAUUGUAAAGUUGCCCUGAGCCUUAAAAUGUCUUACUAGCACACUCCAAUUUAUAUAACAGCUUAUCAAAGAAGAGAAUCAGCAGACAUGCUUCUCAUACUUGAAACUUUAAACAUUGUAGCUAAACGAUAAUUAACUAGGAUUCUGACUCCUUUAUUUAUCUACUGCCACUCCCCCCACACCCCAAUGCCCAGCAGAAGUAUUUAGCAGCUGAACAUUGAUAUUCUGUGAAAAGAUGAAAGAAUUAAACUUCUUUAAUCAAAUGUUGGCCAAUACUUUUUGGCAUUCAGGAUGGACAGAGCCAUUUUUAUAGACUGAGGAUUAGCAGAACAGCUGUACUGUAAGGUUUCUGUGAUGGCAUGAAACUCUUACAGGUGUAUAAUGGCAUUUAGUUACCUACCCUUUGUGUGGCACUAAAAUAGUUCUGUCUAGAUUUAAACACAGCUUCCUAUCUUCUGUCUUUUAUUCUUUCUGUUUUAAUAUUUUUGAGCAAUAGAAGCAAGGAUACUAGCUCUUUACAUUUGUUGACAUCAAUUGGAAUCAGUUUCCUAGAGUUAUGAAGGGCUUAUAUGAGUCCAUUUCGUUUGAUUCCCUUGGGAAACAUAGGCCCUAAAGGGAAAGUGACUUGCCCAAGGUCACAUAACUAGAGUCAAAACUGGGAUGAUAGUUGCUCUAACUCCUAGUUGGGUGCCCAUUCCCCCAACUACCUCCUGGGACCUUUUGCGAGGGAGCAAGAUGGAGCUCCACAUUAGAACUUUUGCAAAGUAGAGGGCUCAGCUCUGCAUCAUUUUGUUCUACUCUGCCUGUAUUUUGACCACAGUAAGUUUAACCGUGUGUUCCUUAUUCUUCCUGAACUUCACUUUCAGAUUUGGAGUAUACUUUGAAGGAAUUUUAGCCCAAAUUCAACUUGUUUAUUUUAAGUUGUUCAACUUAAGUUUAUCUUAUCUUGUAUAUUAGUUUUAGUAUACAAAAAUAACUUUUUAAAAAAGUUGAUUGGGUAUUAAAUUAAUACUGCUACAAGCUUGGUUAAAAUUUCUAGUGCCCUGGUGCACCCUCUGCUGGCUUUACAGUGACAUUUAAUUUUCAGUAUCUGCUGACACUCAGAAUUCUACAUUGUGCUGACAGAUUCUGAUUCAGUAAAUAAGGAAGUAAACAGCCUUGUGGGAUUUGGCCACGUAGGUCAUAUUUUUAUAUUUUAGUUUUUAAACACAAACAACUGCUGUUACAGCAAAUCUUGGAUGGAGAGGAAGAAAGAUAAAAAUAUACACCCUUCAACGGGCAGUACAUUCAGGUUUCUUACCAGUUUAUCUGUAAGGAGUGAAGGCAAGCUGAUGAGAGUAAACUGCAGGAAGCUCUCAUGAGACCAAGUGGGCAGAACAGUCAGAGACACUUCAUGCAGGUAGGCAAAAGUAAACCUAUCCAUACUUAUGAGAUGAUGGGCUCUGGGCUCUCAGUUAUGACUCAAGAAAGGGACCUGGAAAUCACUGUAGAUGUAUGUAUAUCAUCUGUCAAUUUAAAAACUUUUUAAGCAGGGCACACAAGGAAGUUAGGGCAGGUAGGAUACAGAGCAGAGAGAUCAGCACAGUUCUCCAUGUGAAAUGUUAGAAAAGUCUCCCUGGUGGGGACACACUUGCUGAUGAUGAAGUGAGAGAGUCACAUCAGACCUUCCGUAAUCAAUCAUCUCCUUCAGCUGGAGCAACCAAGUAGCUGAGAUUUGUCUGGAUAGUUGGUGGAGAUUAUCUCAAGAGCAAGGGAUAUCUCAUUUGUGUCUGAAUUAGGACAAUAUACAGUAAUAUGAUCGUCAGAGUAAAAAACUAAAAAUCACUGUUGAUCAUUCUGUGGAGAUGUUGCGCCGGUUGUGAUUGUGGUCCUCAAAGGCCAAGAAUGUAGUGGGUAUCAUCAGGAAGGGUGUCAAAAACAACAAAACAAACCACUUACAAAACACUUAUUUUUUCCAUGUACAAGAUCAAAAGCAGAUUGGCUUCUACAAUCAGACAGGAAAUUCUGGUGGCUGCUCCUCAAGAAAAGCCUAACAGCUGAUAAAAGUCCUCAAAAACCCCAUUAAAUUGAUCAAAAGGAUGAAGGGAUUUUCUAGUUGGUUUUUCAGUCUGGAUAGAAAGAGGUUGAAGGAGGAAUAUGAUCAAAGUCUACCAAACCAUGAGCGAGAUGAAUAUGAUUAAUAUAUUGGUGUAACGUAACAAUCCAGUUCAAUAAAUAGAAAGCCUGCUGUGCCAGACACAAUGUUAAGUAUUAGACACCUUUUAAUGUUUGAAAAAUUAUUUUCAAGAGGAGGCAAAUAAAGGUAGUAUCUUAUUCAACUCAUUGUCUCAAGUAAUAGUCAAAAUUAUGGGUAGAUCAAUACAGAUUUACUUAGAACUGUUAGGGCUAUUUGGAGUAUGUUCCUAAUUAUUUGAAGUGAUGUCAUAGAUGUCAACCUUAAAGUUCUACAAAACAUUGCUUGACAUAACUAGAUAGACCAUUAGUGUAUCCAGAGUUGACAUUACCUGUGUUAAGGCUCUUCGAUCAAGAACAUAACUAGGAAUCAUUCGAGGUGAUUCAAGGUGAGCACAAUGAAUAAAUCCAAGGAUUUUUUUUUUUAGGGAGGUGGGAUCUAGAUAAAAUACCUUUACUGUGGGUUUGAAUACAGAACUUUUGAUCAACUUGCUUCAUUAUUCCCAUCGCAUUUUCUCUCUCACUAACUCUGCUGCAACCCACCCAUCAUAUCCUGUCUUAGAAUCAUUCUUUAGUUGUUAUUGCUGUUGUUUUCAAAUACAUUUUAUGUCUUUACAUUAGAGCUCCUUAGAAAUCUGCCUUCAUUUUUGUCUUUCUCCAUAAUGCCUGACACAGUGCUAGUUACAGUUACUGUACUCAAAUACUUGUUGAGUUGAAUAUUAUUUUGGGACUUUGGAGGUGUUUAUGUGAAACAAAGACAUUUUCUCUUUCUAUAACAGGCCUGUUUUCCUCAGGUCUUGCUAAGCCUGUGACCUGUCAGCUAUGCUUAGGUGAGUAAAUAGUUCCACUGGAAAUGUUUCACUGAUUUCUAGAAUAAUUAGAAAGUGAAAUGGAGAAGAGCCUUAACCACGUGGUCAGUCUCCCAGUUUCACACCUUCUCUCUAAAAUGGUGCAAAAAGCUUCCUGUAAUAUAUUGUUUGAUGUUUUGUUUUAUUUGCUUUUAGGUCUCAUGUCUUUCUUUCUAUCUUAGAUCUUGUGAAAAAAUAAUCUGUAAUUUAUCUGUAACUACCUUAUAGAGAAGAUCUCUUUAAAGUAAAGAACCUCUGAAGCCAUUUAAUUCCCAAGAACAUUACCAAGAGAAACCACCUUGCCUGUAGAGGACCAUUUUAUCUAACUCCUCUGUAAAUACUCAGGACUUAGCUUUUCAUUUCAUUUCUUUCUUUUAUUAAAAAUCUUUUCUAUUGAAGUAUAACUCAUACACAGAAAAGUAUAUAAAUCAUAUUUGUACAAUUUGAUGAAUCAUUACAAAGUGAAUAUACUCACGUCACCAGCACCCAGGUCAAGAAAUAGAACAUUAUUAUAUGCCACAACUCCUCCUUACACCCUAUUGUUAUCACUAUAUCCUCCUCACUCUCUCAAGUUCUGACAUCAUAGAUUAGUUUUUUUAUCUUUCUCCAUAGUGCCUGACAUAGUGCUAGUUGGAUUAGUUUAUUAGUUUUGUUCAUUUUGAACUUUAUAUAAAUGAAAUCAAACAGUGUGUAUUCUUUUGGAUCUGGUGUUUUUUGCUCAAUACUGUUUUCGUGACAUCCAUUCAGGUUGUUGCUUGUGGCUGUAGUUUUUUAUUUGUAUUUUUUGUGUGUGUGAGACAGAGUCUUGCUCUGUCACCCAGGUUGGAGUGCAGUGGCAUGAUCACAGCUCACUGCAGCCAUAACCUCCCAGGAACAAGCGAUCUUCCAACCUCAGCUUUUUGAGUAGCUGGGACCACAGGCACAUGCCACCAUGCCUCAUUUUUAAUUUUUUAUAGGCUCAUUUUUAAUUUUUUUAUAGAGACAGGAUCUCUCUAUGUUGCCCAGACUGGUCUUGAACUCCUGGCCUGAAGCAAUACUCCCACCUCAGUGUACCAAAGUGAUGGGAUUACAGAUGUGAACCACCAUGCCCAGCCAUUUAUUUGUAUUUUUGUAUAUUAUUUCGUUGCUCGAAUAUACCACAGUCUAUUUACUCUAUUUUUAAUGAAUUUGUGGAUUGUUUCCAGUCUGGGGCUAUUACGGAUGCUGAUGUUGUGAAUAUUAUUAUACAUGUCUUUUGGUUACAUAUGCUUGAAUUUCUAUUGCUUGUAUAGAUCAGAGUUGCUGGGUCAUGGAGGAUGCAUAUUUUUGACAUUAUUGAUAAUGACAGUUUUUCUAAGUCAUUGUAUCAAUUUACAUGCUCACCAGCAAUGUAUGAGAAUUUCAGCUGUUUCACAUUCUUACUAACACUUGGUAUUGCCAGUCUUUUUAGCCAUAGCUGUUCUGGUGGGUGGCUUUGUAGUAAUAUCCGUUGAUUUUAAUUGGCAUUUCUCAGAAGACUGAUGAGGUUGUGCUCUUUUUCAUGUUUAUUAUGCAUUUGCAUAUCUUCUGUGAAAUGCCUAUACAAGUUUUUUGCCCAUUUUUCUAUUAGUCUGUCUUUUUCUUAUAGAUUUGUAGGAAUUCUUUAUAUACUCUGAAUAUGAACUAUUUUUGUAUUUUUUAUGUUGUAAGCCAUUCCCAAAUCUGUGAUUUACCUUUCUUUAUGGUAUCCUUUGAUGAACAGAAGUUUUUAAUUUUAAUGUGUUUAAUUUUUUAGUAUUUUCCUUUAUGGAUAGUGUUUUCUGUGUCCCAUUUAAGAAAUAUUUUCUUACCUUGAAAUUGUAGAUAUUCUCCCAUAUUAUCUUCUAGAAGCUUUAUGUUUUUGACAUUUACAUUUAGGUCUAUACUCCACUUGAAAUCGAUUUUUGUGUAUGCUAAGAUACAGAAACUAAGCUUCAUUUUUUAAAAUAUAGAUAUCCAACUGAUCCAGUACCAUUAAUUAUAAGGACUGUCUUUCCCCCAGUCCUCUAUAGCAUCACCUUUGUCAUAAAUCAGGUGCCUGUAUAUAUGCAAGAUUGUUUCUGAACUGUUUAUUCUAUUCUGUUGGUCUCUUUGUCAUUACAUCACUACCACAAUCUUAAUUACUGGACUUUAUUAUUACCUGGUAAAGCAACUCCUUUCACCUUGUUCCUCUUAUUUAAAAGUAUCUUGGAUAUUCUUGGCCCUUUGCAUUUAGAAUCAGCUUGUCAUGUUCCACAAAAAAGAAACGUGCUGAGAUUUUUAUUGGGAUUGCAUUGCAUCUAAAAAUCAAUUUAGAGGGAACUCACCAUUUUAUGGUAUUCAGUUUUCCAAUCCAUGAACAUGCCCAGCAGAUUUGGUGUUUGGUGAGUGCCUUCUUCUUGAUCCAUAGAAUGACACACUCUUGCUGUAUCCUCACGUGGUGGAAGGGAUAAAUGCACUUCCUUGGACCUAUUUUAUAAGGACAUUAAUCUCAUUUACAAGGGCUCUGCCCUCAUUAUUUAAUUGCCCCCUAAAAGCCUCAUCAAAUACCAUCACAUUGGUGAUGAUAUUUCAACAUAUGAAUUUUGGGGGGAACACAAACAUUCAGACCAUAGCAAACCUAUUUUAGACAUUUUCUCAGCAUCCUUUAUGUCUGUUACAUACUUUUCUCUGUAUUCUAUCCUUCUUUUUCUCUCUAUACUUCAUUCUAGGUAUUUUCUUUUUUUUCUUUUUUUUUUUUUGAGACAGUUGCAUCUACAUACUUUAUUUUCAAAAAAUCUUCACAGGAACAAUGCAAGGUAGAUAUUGCCGUGUCUCUAUUUUUACAUGUGGAGAAGCAGACCCAGAGGGGUUAAAUAACUGUCUGCAAUCAUAUAGCUAUUUCUGGAACUGUGUUUUAAAUAGGAAUUUUAUAAACCAUAUAUAGAACUUGUAUCAACUGGACCAUUUAAAAUGUGCAUGGAGAAGUUUCUAUUUAAAGGACUCCCAUGAAAGGUAGAUUAAUUCAAUAAGUAGUAUUGGGAUUUACUGACUUGCCAUUUUGGGGGUUUAAAAAAAAAGACAAGUAAAACUGGAUCCUUAUCUCACCUCUUAUACCAAAAUAAAUUCCAGAUGGAACAAAGAUUUACAUGUAAAACAUGAAGUCACAGACAUCCUAGAAGAACACAUGGAUGCAUAUUUUUAGAAUCUUACAUUCUGGAUAUUUUCCUGUGACUUAACUUCCAAUUCAUUAAUUCUGUCUUCAGCUUUGUCUAAACUCCCUUUAAACUCACUCAUUGAGUUCUUAAUAUUAUUUGUCAUGUUUUUUAUUUUUAGAAUUUUCAUUUGGUUCUUUUUAUAAGAUAGUGUUUGGUUCUCAGCCAAACUCUGCCAAAAUAUCUUUUAACAUACUGGCCAUAAUUAUUUGAAAAUCUUCAUUUGAUUACUCAUUAUUUCAAUCCUUGAGGGUACGUUUCUAUUGUCUAUUGUUUGUCUUAAUUUUCUAUCACUUUACCUUUCUCCUGGUUAGUUUUGAUUGAAUGGUAGACAUUAUAUAUGAAAGAUUAUAGUAGAGAUGGUUUGAGACCUCAGUUAUUUUUAUCUUUAUCUAGAAAGGAUUUAUACUCACUUCUGGCACGUGGUUAGAGACACUAGCAAUCUCACAUCUCCUUAAUUCAAUAUGAGACUGAGAUAAUUUAAAGCUGCCCUUCAAUCCAAGUGAAGGUUGACUUACCCUUCCUUUUAGUAUUUAUGCCUUCUAAGUUGAAACCCAAAGCUUGGGUUUUUUUUUCCCCUUGGGAGUUCUCCCUCUUUGAAGGGUCCUUAAUUCCAAUUUUUGUUCUUGUAGCUUCAUGAGUCUGUCAGAAGCUCCUCUCUCUCUCUCUCUCUCUCUCUCUCUCUCAGCUGACUCUACUAUAUCAGCCAAUGACCUUAGGAGAAAAACAGCCUCUCUCAGUUUUCUUUUUAUCCUGCAUUUUGGCUUUAUAGUAUUGCAUUACUUUGUUAGAUCUCAGAUAUCUUCAAACAUAUAUCAUUUAUAUCUUGCCCCAAUUUUCUUGUGUUUUUUUAAGCAGGAAAUUUAGCCCAAAUUACUUUUGCUUCCAUUACUAGAAGCAGAAUCAGCUUAUCAUUUCUUCAACAAAUGUUUAUUGAUCAUCUCCUGUGUAUCAUGCACUGUACAAAACAAUGGAGAUGCAGCUGUUGAACAGAUUAGAGGGGAUUCCUGCCAUUGUGGAGCAUACAGACAAGUGAACAGGCACAUAUAAUACAAUUUCAUAAAGCAAUGGUAGGGUUAAUCAUAGGAUGAUGUAGAGCACUAAGGAGGAGUGCCUGACCAUGACUUUUGAAAUCAAGGAACAUGUUCUUGACAAAGCAUCUUCUGAGCUUAAACCUAAAAAGUAAGUAAGAAUUAUCUAGGAUAAGACUGUUUUAGGCAGUAGGAACAGCAAGUGCAAAGGCCUGGAGAUGAAAGAGAACAUGGUACAUCCAGGAAUAAGAAAACCUAGUUUGUAUGAAGCUACUAUUAUCAAGACAGGGUGGUUCUGGCAUGAGGACAGGCAUAUAUAUCAAUGGAACAGGACUGAGAGGUCAAAAAUAAACUCUUAUAUUUAUAAUCAAUUGAUUUUUGACAAAAGUACCAAGAUGAUUAGUUGGGGGGAAAAGAUACCCUGUUCAAUAAAUGAUGUUGGGAAAAUUGGAUAUCCACAUGCAAAAAAGAUGAACUUAGAUACUCACUAGAGACCAUACCCCAAAAAUGAACUCAAAAUGGAUCAUAGGCUUAAAUGUAAGUACCAAAACAAUAAAAUGUUUAGAAGAAAACAUAGAAAAUCCUUAAGAUCUUGCAGAGCAAAGAUUUAUUAGAUAUGACACCAAACACAUAGUCUAAAAAAGAAAUGAACCGUUUUGGAAAGAAACUUUUUUUUUUUUUCAAAAGAAAACCUUGAAAAAUGAAAAGAAAUGCAACAGACUAGGAGAAAAUCUUUGGAAAACAUAUAUCUGGUAAAUAACUUAUAUUCAAAGGAAUUUACAAAGGAUUCUUGGAAUGUAAUAAUAAGACAAACCAAACAAAAAAAUGAGCAAAAGAUAUGAACAGAUAUUAUACCACAAAUGAAGAUACACAAAUGGCUAAAUAAAUACAUGAAAACAUGUUCGACAUCAUUAUCCAUUACAGAAAUUUAAAUUAAAACCACAGUGAGAUACCAUUUCACACCCACUAGACUGGCUAUAAUGAAAAAGACAAUAAGAAGUGGAGAUGUGGAGAAAUGGAAACUCUCAUACAUUGCUAGUGGAAAUGUAAAAUGAUUCAGCUGUUUUGUAAAACAGUUUGUCAGUUCCUCAAUAAGUUAACAUAGAAUUACAAUAUGACCCAGCAUUUCCACUCCUAGGCAUAUACCUAAGAUAAUUGAAAACGUAUGUUCACACAAAAGCCUCUACAUUGAAUGUUCAUAGCAGCAUUAUUCAUAAUAGUCAAAAAGUAAAACAGCUCCAAUGUCUGAUGUGGUAUAAUGUGAUAUAAUAUUCUAUACAAUGCAAUAUUUUUCAGCCAUUAAAAGGAAUGAAUUAUGAAUAAUGCUACAACAUGGCUGAGCCUCAAAUAUAUUAUGCUAAGUGAAGGAAGUUAGUCACAAAAAAACCACAUUGUAUGAUUCCAUUUAUAUGAAAUGUCCAGAAUAGGCAAAUAUAUAGAGACAAAAAUUAGAUUACUGGAUGCCUGGGGCAGGGGGUAGGAAUUAGGAUUAACUGAAUAUGGGCAUAAGGGCACUUAUUGGGGAUGAAAAUAUUCUAAAACUGAUUUACCACAGCCAGGGUUAUAGCAGUGGAACGAAAUAAAGGAAAUGAUGCAAGAGAUAUCAUGAAGUUACACAAUUCUGUAAAGUUACUAGAAAUUAUUGAAUUGUACACUUAAAAUGGAUGAAUUCUACAGUAUGUGAAUUAUAUCUAUAUAAAGUAGUUUUUUUUAAGUGUCUGGCACAUAGAAGAUGGUGAAUAAAUGUGUAAGGGGCGUUGGUUGUUUCUGAAUGAUACCUAUCUUUAGAGGAAGAGAAUCUUCAAGGCUAUUCGAUUUACUUCAGAGAUUUCUCCCUCUAACAGAUGUGUCCAGGGUCCCAGUGCAGAAUCAAUUGAAUUAGAAGCUUCAAGGAUGGGAGUCUAGUCGUAUAUAAUUUGACAAAGCCCUAUGGGUGAUUUUGCCAAGCACUGCAAAUUGAGACUCUGUGAUUUAUGGAAUUGUGAAUGGCUUAGUAUGGUCAGAACUCAGGGUGCAUGUGGGACCCAAUAGGUACUUGCACUAGAGUGGGCAGUAAUCAAGAAUCUUGGCCCAGAAUCAUCUCUGUCUUCCUCGCUUUCCCUUUUUUCCUCUCUACAUCCCUCUCCCUUUCUGCCUCCCUGCCUCUCUCUCUGCUUCUUACUCUUAUUCUCUCUGAUAGAAAUAGCUAGCUAGCUAUUCCCAGAUCCUACUUAGAAUUUUUUUCAGAAUUGUAGGGUUAAAAUAUAUCAUACAGAUCAUCCGUGGCAGUGGUUCUUAACCAGGGAUGCAUAUUAGUCUUACCUGGAGAACUUUUUCAAGAUACACAGGUCCCUGGCCACACCCAGACAUACAUCAUUAGAAUCUUUAGAGUGAGACCAUGGGCAUAUAUAGUUUAUAAAAAGGUUUUUCAGGUGAUGCUGAUGCUCAUCUCCAUUUGAGAACGUACUGCUCUAAAGGAAGAAAUAAAAGCAUAAAGAAGAUAAGAUUUGGUUCCCCAUGCCUAACUUCAGCUUCCCUGUUACAGAUUAUUAGGUCUGUAUCACCUGUGUUACUGAAGCUACUUUUGAAGACCACUAGACCUGAGCUUGGGUGGUAGUGAAUGCUUAAUGAACACCACUGUGGAAUACCAUUUGGAAAAUCAAUUCAUAAACUCUGGGGAGAGAGGGAUUAGAUUUCAGUUGCCAUUUCCUCAGCCAGAUGAUAGUGCUGUGUGCUUGGAAUAGCCAAGAAAGGAGGGUGGUUUCCUGUCUCUUGUGGCUUCCUGGUGACUUCUCUUGGUGCUAGCUGCUGAAACCACUUUAAAAUAAUAGGCUGUUGAGUAAUUUUCUCCAUGUAUAUCCACCUGUCAGUGGGCCUGCACUUCAGAGAUGAAGAGUAGUUUUUAUUGGCGUGAUGGCAUAUAGCAGGGAUUGAAACCAAACAGCCGCAAUGAAAUUGAUUUUCAAAAAGAAAUUACUUCUGAAUUUUAUUCUGUGGUUUGUGGAUUGUUAUUCUUACUUCAUCCUGCCACACCAGUGGCCUACAAGGACAAUGAAAGCUUGGACAUAAGUAAGAGUUUUGGAUCAAUCCACAAGGCUCUGUACCUAGAAAAAUUGCAUGCUGCGAAAGCACUUUUGCUAUGUAGUCUAAAUGUUGGGGAAACUCUGAGAGUUUCUUCUGUAAGGAUGGACCUUAACACCUGCCACAACUAGUCAGACUGAGGGAAAGAAGGGCAAAGAGUAGCUUUCAGGAGUUCUUUCGACUCAACCCCCACUCCAUUGAGUCCCUAUUUGGUAUGAGAUAAUGCUAGUAGGGGGAUUGUAUCCUCAAGACAGAUUCAGCUAACAGAACCAAUGAAGGAGCACAAACCUACUUCAUCCUUAAUGACAUUAGACAAAUCCUUUGGUGCAGCUUGUUUCUGUUUGGAUUCCCAGCUGACAUCUCAAAUUUAGUAAGCUAAACUGAACUUAUCUUCAUUCUUCCCCUUCCCACCACACACACCAAAUUUUAUAAAAGUAAACCCUGGUUUCAUGCUCUCAAUCACUUAUGCAUAAAACUUGGAAGGCCUUAUAUUUUUACUUCUCCCUUGUCCUUGCUACCUAUAUAUAGCAAUCAAUUGUUAAGUUGACUCCUACUUUGUGAUGUUGAUUUAUAUUGUUCAUGAUGUCUCUUGCAUGACUCCCUUUCUUUCUAGUCUCACUGCUAUCACUCUGGCUGUAUUUGGCUUAGAUGAUCUUCAAGGUGCCUCCCAACAAUGAAAAUCUGUGACUCUUUCUCAGCUCCUUAUUACCUCACUCCUACAGUGGUUGUGUAGCUGAGAGUUGCUUUGUUCUCUGUUCCAUAUAUAUACCUCAGCUAGAUUAUUUUUCUUCCAGAGUUAUUUUGUUAUGUCACUUCCUCCUCAGAAACCUUGACAUCUCCCUACUGCCCGUAGAAUAAAGUUCAGACUUCUUAAACUGGCAUUCUAAGCCCCUUUGCAAUUGGGUUUGAACUACUCUGUCACUCUUCUUUUUAUUCUCUGUUUGAAUCUUGUUUUAUCCAGACUGGUCCACUGACAGGCCGCGUUCUGGCCUUUGUUUGUUUACCUGUUCCCCCGAAGAAGAAUGUUCUUUCCUCCAACCUGUCUCUUGGACCCCUCCAGGUCCUUCAAAGCUCAACUUAAACCUUAACUCUUGUGUGCAUUCUUCCUUGCCCAUCUAUCCAUCCCAGCACCCUAAAUUCCUCAUUCAGCACUGUGCUGUGUUGUAGGUGUUCUUGUUUCCUUAACUUGAUGUGAAGGUUUUUGAAGACAGAGACUGAGUGUUACAUUCCUUUAUAGCUCUUAUACCUACAACGCUAACUGUACUCUUUUAAUUAAAUACCAAAGUGAAUCUUAAGGUAUUGAAACAUUCCCCCUAAUAUCGGACUCUAAAAUAUAGUUGUACACAUUGAUUGUGAGGAUUAUCAUGCUACCUUAAGGAUCUGGUGAUUAUUAAUGGAGUCUGUCAGUAGGGCUUCUUUGCUUUUAGAGCCCUGCUUAAGGUCAAGCACCCUCACAGAAAGUUUCUUAGACUCUAGAGCUUCCUUCCUCAGUUCCUUUCCCUCCUUCAGAUCUUUAAAAGCCUUCCACAUAACAAGUAUUCAUAUUCCACUUUGACCUGCUGUAUACCUCUUGAUUUCCUCAAUACAGCAAGUCCUUACCUUCAAAAUGCUUUCGGAAUUCAUUUCUCCCUGAAUACUGAAGGUACCUCAACUUCUUGGCUUUCAGAUUCUAACUCACGUGCCAGGUCACGAGAGGCUCCAUACCCAAGUUUCUUUUCAAGUCACAAACCCCAUACACCCCCAUCGUAUAUCAAAGUUCCCUAACCCUCUUGUUUGUAUUUUUAACAGUAACUCAUUUAAACGUGUAAAUGUGGGAAAGCCCUUAAGGUCAGGACUCUCUCUGUUUGUCUUGUAUAGUGCAAAAUAUGCCGGUGUUCCAAAUAAUAAAGGUUUAGGGAAAAGCCCAGGUUGUGGUUAUGUACGUGUCUGUGUUUGUCUGUGUGAGGGAGUCAAGGAAGGGGAGGGGGAGAAAAUGGAGGGACUGACUUGUGUUUCUUUGUGUUUGCGUAUAAGUAUUAAAUGCUAGAAUUCUAGCAUUUAAUUUCUAGGAGAAAUGUGAUUCAUAGUUCAGGACAUAAGACCAAGUAGUACUACUGUUUCAUAAACUACACUCUUACAUUUCCAGUUAACCCAUUUUCUUCUCAGCCCCUGACUUUACCUAUUCAUUCAGAAAGUCUGGCUCCCACCUGCUAAACCAGAGUGCCUCAUGCUUAUUUUGGUCUGUUUUGGAUAUCUUUCUUAUCCUGGAGGUUGUAGAAAGAGUACUGGAAUAAGUUCUGGCUCUUAACCAACUAGCAUAUUUCAGUGUCCUUAUUUGUAAAAUGGGAAAGACAGUACCUUCCCUGUCUCCUUCGCACUGUCUUUUUGAGGAUCAAACACAAAUAUGUGUGAAAAAUAUAAAGUCUUGUGGUUAUUUCUUAGAGGACUAUUUGAUAAAUCUGUCUCUUUGUCUCGUUAAUUAUGUAAAACUUUUUUUCUAAUUACUACCUUAUAUUUUCCAUAUAGUUGCCCUGUCUGUUGACAUAAAUUCACAGGGGUUGGUAAUGGUACUGCAUUUUUUCAAAUCGUGCUUUUAUGUUAUACUCCCUUUUUGCAUUUACAAAUGCUUUCUUUCAGCCUGGCCCUCUGACAAUUUAUUUCCACAAGUUGUAGAGGGAUAACUGGAUUGGAAAUUGGGAUACAGUAGUACUGGUCCCAGGUCUGCGUUUAGUUAUUCUCUUCUAGUUAAGUUGGUUCACCUUAGGUAGGUCAUUUCAUCUUUCUGGCUCUCUGUUUACUUAUCUGCAAAAUGUUGGAGAUUGAAGUUGGUGAUCUAUAAGUUCUCUUCAAACACUAACAAUUUAUCAUUGCAGCUAAAUAGAAUUCCUGAUGCUGGCCAGGCACGGUGGCUCACACCUGUAAUCCCAGCAUUUUGGAAGACUGAGGUGGGUGGAUCACCUGAGGUCAGGAGUUCGAGACCAGCCUGACCAACGUGGUGAAACCCCGUCUCUACUAAAAAUACAAAAAUCAACUGGGUGUGGUGGCACGCACCUGUAAUCCUAGCUACUUGGGAGGCUGAGGCAGGAGAAUCAGCUUGAGCCCAAGAGGUGGAGGUUGCAGUGAGCCAAGAUCGCACCACUGCACUCCAGCCUGGGUGACAGAGCGAGACUCCGUGUCAAAAAAAAAAAAAAAAAAGAAUUCCUGAUGCUUUUUUUUCAGUUUUUCCUGCUCCACACCCCGCUCCUUGAGAAUCACUGGCCUAAUGAAUAUAGUCCAGAUGCCAAAUUCAAGACCUACAUCAGUGUUGGCUUGCCAGUAUUAUGUACUGUUUCCAACAAGAACCCCCGGUUAUAUAUAGAUUGGUUUUCUUACUGCACAUUCCUACCUUCAUUGCCACUGUGUCAUUCCCCCUGUUAAAAUCUUUUUUUUUUCUUUUUUUUUUUGUGGUAGAAUACUCCUUUGUCUCUAAGGACAAGCUUAAAUGUUAUACUUUCCUGUGAAGCCUUUCCUAAUAGCUUAAACCUUAGUAAUAUUUUUUCUAUUUCAUCUGAACCACAUCUGCAUUUAUGAUAUGCCAGACACUAUACCUGGCAUUGUAGGAGACAGAAAGAUAAAAUAAGUUCCUCACAUUAGAGAAGGCUGAAAUUGGGAAUUAGCAUUCUGGGCAGUGGUUAGCAGCAUCAGCAAAGACUUGGAAAUAGUAGAGUGGAGUAGAGUAGAGGGUGAGUUUGGAUAAAGGCUUAGAGCCCAUGGACCUUACUUAUUUGGCCUAUAACUAUAUAUCCUCUUAUGACAGUUCUUGUGAUAGUAUGCUACCUUAUAAUAUGAAAUUGUGGUUUAUUUGUCAUUUAUUGGCUACCUAGCUUUCAUUUCCUUUUCCUAAUACCAUUGCAGUUUCUUUUUGGAGUAGUCCCUUUCCAUUAUUGGAUGGUGUAAUAGGAAAUCUAGGUGCCUGUAUCCCACAAGAGAAGCCAAAGGGGUCAAGUCCUUCUACUUACUACCCCAGUAAAAUCAAAGAGCAGUAGCCAUGUGAUGUAUGGUCAACCAACCUACAUUCUCUUGUGGGGCUGGCUUGACUUUUUGUCUUACAGUCUAUAUCCUUUGGCCCAUUGCUCCAAUCACCCUCUUGCAAUUACCUCAAGUCUCUUGACUCUCUGUCCCCAGGUCCCCCUGUCUUAACAAAACCUCAGUCUAGGAUUAGCCCUACCAUUUGGCUUUAUCAGUUCUACAUGAAAGACUGUUGAAUAGGACUGCAGAGAAUAACCAAUUACAGCCACUACAAAUUCAGGCCCCAACCUCUGCUGGAUACUUAGUUACCUAGCAAUCUUUCUUUCUGUGGACUGAAUUAGCUUGAUCUUCUGAACUCAGCAGCAAUUCUGUACUCUCACUUUGGUCCUCAGACCUCCUGCUCUAAGACAUACUUCACUUUCAGCUGUUAAAACCCAAUUCCUACUUCACUGAAAACAAUCAAGACUAUCUGUGACAUCAUCUGCAAAUCCAUUCCCCUCACUAACUAUAAUACCACCUAUGGAUUUUACUCCAUUUGCCCCCACUCUUGUGCUCCUGUCUCCAUAGAGGAAAUGUGUUCCUUUGGUUCAAGACCAGUCCUUUUAUCUGAGCUUUGGAUCUUCUCCCCGCUUACUAUCUCAUGGUCCUUUCUCUUAGUCAUUUUCUUCCUAUCCUGUAUCUUGGAUCUCUCUCAAACUUCUUUUUUUCCUCUUAGCAUGUAGUCAUGCUCACAUCUCAUCUUUGGGGGGGACCUUUUUUGACCCAAAUCUUCCUAAAACUACCCUUUCCUACUUCUGUAAAUAGUUAAGCUUCUGAAAAGAGUGGAAUAAACUUGCUGUCUUUACGUUUUAACCACUCAUUGAUACCUAAUCCUCCUGUGGUUCAGCUUCUGUGUCCUCCUCCCAGGAGUUUGUGCUUGCUCACCAGUGACCUUCAUAUUGUAAAAUUUAACGGGACACAUUUAUUCUAAUCAUAUUUCACUUAUCUGUCAAGUCCUUUAUUUUAUUAUUUAAAAUUUUUGAUAAUAAGCAGAGAAAGCCACUUGACAUUAUGAAUUUACUGGGGAUAGUUAUUUCAAUGAUUAAUGUUCCUCAGUGAAUAUUUAUUAUGAAGUUUCAAUUUUGUUUUAGAAUUUUGUAAUUGAGAUAUAAUUUACAUAACUUAAAAUUCAUCCUUUUAAAGUGUACAAAACACUAGUUUUUAGUAUAUUCACAGAGUUGUGCAACUGUGACCAUUGUCUAAUCCAAGAACAUUUUCAUUGCCCCCCAAAGAAACUGUAUCCAUUAGCAGUCAUUCCCCAAUUCCUCCUUUCCCCCAUCCUCUAUCAACCACUAAUCUACUUUCUGCCGCUAUGGAUUUACCUAUGCUGGACAUGUCAUAUAAAUGGAAUCAUGUAAUAUGUGGCUUUAUGUGUCUGGCCUUCUUCACUUAGCAUAAUAUUUUCAAAAUUCAUCCAUGCUGGAACAUGUAUCCGUCCUUUUUCCCUUUUACAGGUGAAUAAAAUUCCAUUGUAUGGAUAUACCACCUUUUAUUUAUCUAUUUUGUCUAUUGAUGAACAUUUGAGUUGUUUCCACCUUGGGGUAUUAUGAAUAAUGCUGCUAUGAACAUGGAGGUGUACAGGUUUUUGUUUAAACACCUGUUUUCCAUUCAUUUGGGGUAUAUACCUAGUGGUGGAAUUGCUGGGUCCUAUGUUAAUUCUAUGUUUAACUUAUUGAGGAACCACCAAGCUGUUUUUCACAAUUGUUGAACCAUAUUACAUUGUCACCAGCAGUGUAUAAGGGUUCCAGUUUCUCCACAUCCCUGCCAACGCUUGUUGUGAUCUUUUUUAUUAUAGCCAUCUUACUGAGCAUAAGGUGAUAUCUAAUUGUUUUGAUUUGCAUUUCCCUAAAGACUAAUGAUAUUGAGCAUUUUUUCAUAUACAUAUUGGCCGUUUGUAUAUCUUUGAAGAAAUGUCUAUCCAAAUCCUUUGUCCAUUUCUAAAUUGCAUUAUAUGCCUUUUAAUUUUUGAAUUGCAAGAGUUCUUAAUGUAUUCUGCAUACUAAACCCUUAUUAGAGAUAAAAUUUGCAAAUAUUUUCUCCCAUUCUAUGUGUUGUAGUUCUUUAUUUUUAUUUUAUCCUGAGGCAGGGUCUCACUCUGUUGCCCAGGCGGGAGUGCGGUGGCAUGAUCUCGGCUCACUGCGACCUCCAUCUCCUGGGCUAAAGUGAUCCUUCCGCAUCAGCCCCCUAAGUAGCUGACAUUACAGGCUUGCACCACCAUGCCCGGAUAAUUUUUUUAUUAUUUUUUUUAAUAGAGAUGGAGUUUCCCCAUGUUGGCCAGGCUGGUCACGAACUCCUGACCUCAAGUGAUUCGCCCACCUCGGCCUCCCAGAGUGCUGGGAUUACAGACAUGAGCUACCAUGCCCGGCCUCCUUAUUUUUUGAACCCUCUCCUCUUUUGGUUUCCAUGGCAAUAGGCUUUCUUAUUUUUUUUUCCUACUUCUCUGACUAUUCCUUCCCAAGUUCUUUUAGAAGGUUCUUUCCUACGUAUCUCUUAAAUGUUGUUACAGUCAUGUGCCACAUAAUGAUGUUUCUGUCAAUGAUGAAGCACAUGUACAAUGAGGGUGGUCCCGUAAGAUUAUAAUGGAGGUGAACAAUUUUUAUUGUCUAGUGACAUCUCAUAGCUGUUGUAACAUUGUAGUACAAUGCAUUACCUUUUCUAUGUUUGCAUAUGUUUAGAUAUACAAAUAUUUACUAUUGUGUUACAAUUAUCUAUGACUUUAUGAAUAUUAUGUACAGUGUUCAGUAUAGUAACAUGUUACACAGGUUUGUAGCCUAGGAGCAAUAGGCUAUACCUGUGUAGUAGGCUAUACCAUCCAGAUUUGUGUAAAUAUACUCUAUGAUGUUCACACAAUGACAAAAUAACCAAAUGACAUAUUUCUCAGAAUGUAUCCCUGCUGUUAAGUGACACAUGACACACUAUUUCCUAGGUCUACACUCUUGCCUUCUUUUCUCUUGUUAGUUUAUAUAUUCUCCCAGUGUGAUCUCUUUUAAAUUCAUGGCUUUUAACUGUCAUCUAUGUAGGAAUGAUUUUGAAGCCAAGAUCUACAGUAUAUACAGUUCAGACCUCUUUCCUGUAUCCCAUAUCUGCUGAGCUCCAGUAGUAUUUCUAUUGGAAAUCUUUUGAGUAUAGCAUAGGCAACUUGAAAUCAAUUUAUCCUAAACUGCAUUUAUCACCUUCCUACCCCAAACCUGCUUUUCCUCCCCUGUUCAUCUCAGUGAGUACUACUACCAUUCAUUUACUUAUCUAAGCCAGAAGUGGAAUUGUUCUAGAUUACUCCUUCUCACUUCCUCCCCACUCACAUUCUAACACCAAAUCUUUUUUUUUUUUUUUUUUUUGACACAGAGUUUCACUCUUUCACCCAGGCUGGAGUGCAGUGGCAUCAUCUCGGCUCACUGCAACCUCUGCCUUCUGGUUUCAAGCGAUUCUCCUGCCUCAGCCUCCUGAGUAGCUGGGAUUACAGGCGCCCGCCACCAUGCCCAGCUAAUUUUUGUAUUUUUAGUAGAGACGGGGUUUCACCAUGUUAUCCAGGCUGGACUCGAACUCCUGACCUCGCUAACACCAAAUCUUAUAGAUUCUACCUUCUUAGUGUUUCUUCAGUUUCUCCUCUCAUUUCAAUACUUACUACCUCAAAGGCCACCACCAACCCAGUUUAGUUUAACUUCUACUUUUUUUUUCAACUUGAGUGUCACCUACUCCAAAAAACUUUCCUUAACUAUUCUUUGCCAGGUCUGAAAUAUAUGCUCUUUGGUGUUCCUAUAAAAUUCUAUGCUUACUCCUGUCACUGCACUUAACUAUAACACACUGUACUCUACUGAUAUAGUUCUGAUGUUUGUCCCCUCCAAAUCUCAUGUUAAAACAUAAUCCCCAAUGUUGGAGGUGGGGCCUGGUGGAAGGUGUUUGAGUCAUGGGGGCAGAUCCCUCAUUAAUGGCUUGAUGUUGUCCUUAAGAUAGUGAGUUCUCAUGAGGUCUGGUUGUUUAAAAGUGUGUGGCACCUCUUCUCCUCUUCCUUGCUCCCUUUCUCACCAUGUGAUGUGCCUACUCCCACUCCACCUUCCAGCAUGAUUUUAAGCUUCCUGAGGCCCUUCCCAGAAGCCAAGCAGAUGUAGGUACCAUGCUUGUACAGCCAGUAGAACUGUGAGCCAAUUAAGCCUCUUUUUAUUAGUAAAUCACCCAGUCUCACAGUCUCAGGUAUUACUUUAUAGUAAUAGUAAUGCAAAAAUGGCCUAAUACAUCUGUGCAUGUUAUUUAACUUGUCUACCUUAUCUAGUAAACUGAAGUCCUUCUCUACUAAACCCCUCUGCUAAACCCCUUUUUGUAUGACUAUGUCCACAAUGCCUAGAACAAUGUCACGCACACCAUAGGUGCUCAAACUGGUUCAUGGUUUUUUUUUUUUUUUUUGAUGCUCAAAC